AGAGCGCGGCGGCGGCGGCCACGGCAACAUCAGCCCAGCCAUCAGCCGAGCAGACGCCCAGCACCCGGGAGCGCGGCGAGCUUCGGCUCAGCCCGGAGUUCACCUCCGAGUGCCCCGGGGGCUGAGCUCACCCCUUCUGCUCUCUCACACACGAACACUCUCUUUCACUCACACACACACACGUAUUCACACUCUCUCGCACACACAUAGGACCCUGGGCGCAAGCACCCUUCUGGCAGCGGUCGUCCGCUGGUGCAAUAGUAGCUAGGUUCGGUUCCUGCCUCCGGCGGCCGCCGGUUUAGAGCACCGCUGCCAGCAGCCGGAGGAGAGCAAUGCGGGGGCCCGAGCGGCAGCUCGAACAGUAAUGUGGAUUUACAGUCGUUUCCCGCAGGAGUCGGCCGAGACGCCCUAAGUCCCGGGCACUGGCAGCGCCCGGCGGAGCCGAGCACCUGGCGAGGGGGCGGGGGAACAGCACCUGGGGACGCCGCCGAAACUUGCGCUUGGAAUAGGAAUUACAAGGGUGACCUUUAUUCCGCUGUCUCCUUUUUGAUUCCCAUAACUUCUGGACCUAUCAAGUGCUAUGCAUCAUUACUCAAAUGUGAAUUCUCAUUUCAAGCUGUAAAAAAGUCAAAAGGAUGAUCUGAAUUUGUGAAGGCCCAACAUCAGGACUUUGUAUUAUUCACCUUGCCUGCUUCCCAGCACUUUUAUCAUGGACACACCUCUGGAGCUGACGACUGCUUGCAUUAAAGGACUUCCUCAUCCUUUUUUUCAUGAAACUGAGCUUGCUUAAUCAGAGAUGGAGCAAACUGACUGCAAACCCUACCAGCCUCUACCAAAAGUCAAGCAUGAAAUGGAUCUAGCUUACACCAGUUCUUCUGAUGAGAGUGAAGAUGGAAGAAAACCAAGACAGUCAUACAACUCCAGGGAGACCCUGCACGAGUAUAACCAGGAGCUGAGGAUGAAUUACAAUAGCCAGAGUAGAAAGAGGAAAGAAGUAGAAAAAUCUACUCAAGAGAUGGAAUUCUGUGAAACCUCUCACACUCUGUGCUCUGGCUACCAAACAGACAUGCACAGCGUUUCUCGGCAUGGCUACCAGCUAGAGAUGGGAUCUGAUGUGGACACAGAGACAGAAGGUGCUGCCUCACCUGACCAUGCACUAAGAAUGUGGAUAAGGGGAAUGAAAUCAGAGCAUAGUUCCUGUUUGUCCAGCCGGGCCAACUCUGCAUUAUCCUUGACUGACACUGACCAUGAAAGGAAGUCUGAUGGGGAAAAUGGUUUCAAAUUCUCUCCUGUUUGUUGUGACAUGGAGGCUCAAGCUGGGUCUACUCAAGAUGUGCAGAGCAGCCCACACAACCAGUUCACCUUCAGACCCCUCCCACCGCCACCUCCGCCUCCUCAUGCCUGCACCUGUGCCAGGAAGCCACCCCCUGCAGCGGACUCUCUUCAGAGGAGAUCAAUGACUACCCGCAGCCAGCCCAGCCCAGCUGCUCCAGCUCCCCCAACCAGCACGCAGGAUUCAGUCCAUCUGCAUAACAGCUGGGUCCUGAACAGCAACAUACCAUUGGAGACCAGGCAUUUCCUGUUCAAACAUGGAUCUGGUUCCUCUGCGAUCUUCAGUGCAGCCAGUCAGAACUACCCUCUGACAUCCAAUACCGUGUACUCGCCCCCUCCCAGGCCUCUUCCUCGAAGCACCUUUUCCCGACCUGCCUUUACCUUUAACAAACCUUACAGGUGCUGCAACUGGAAGUGCACAGCAUUGAGCGCCACUGCAAUCACAGUGACUUUGGCCUUGUUACUAGCCUAUGUGAUUGCAGUGCAUUUGUUCGGCCUGACUUGGCAGUUGCAACCAGUUGAAGGAGAGCUGUAUGCAAAUGGAGUUAGCAAAGGGAACAGGGGGACCGAGUCCAUGGACACUACUUACUCUCCAAUUGGAGGAAAAGUUUCUGAUAAAUCAGAGAAAAAAGUGUUUCAGAAGGGACGGGCGAUAGACACUGGAGAAGUUGACAUUGGUGCACAGGUCAUGCAGACCAUUCCACCUGGUUUAUUCUGGCGUUUCCAGAUUACUAUCCACCAUCCAAUAUAUCUGAAGUUCAAUAUUUCUUUAGCCAAGGACUCUCUGCUGGGAAUUUAUGGCAGAAGAAACAUUCCACCUACACAUACUCAGUUUGAUUUUGUAAAACUAAUGGAUGGCAAACAGCUGGUCAAGCAGGACUCCAAGGGCUCUGAUGAUACACAGCACUCCCCUCGGAACCUGAUCUUAACUUCGCUUCAGGAGACAGGUUUCAUAGAGUAUAUGGAUCAAGGACCUUGGUAUCUGGCGUUUUACAAUGAUGGAAAAAAGAUGGAGCAAGUAUUCGUGUUAACUACAGCAAUUGAAAUAAUGGAUGACUGUUCAACCAAUUGCAAUGGAAAUGGAGAGUGUAUCUCUGGCCAUUGUCAUUGUUUCCCAGGAUUCCUUGGACCUGACUGUGCUAGAGAUUCCUGCCCUGUGCUGUGUGGUGGGAAUGGAGAAUACGAGAAAGGACACUGUGUCUGCCGGCAUGGCUGGAAGGGGCCAGAGUGUGACGUUCCGGAAGAACAAUGCAUUGAUCCAACAUGCUUUGGCCACGGCACCUGCAUCAUGGGAGUCUGCAUCUGUGUGCCAGGAUACAAAGGAGAAAUAUGCGAGGAAGAGGACUGCCUAGACCCAAUGUGUUCCAACCAUGGCAUCUGUGUAAAAGGAGAAUGUCACUGUUCUACUGGCUGGGGAGGAGUUAACUGUGAAACACCACUUCCUGUAUGUCAAGAGCAGUGCUCAGGACACGGAACUUUUCUUCUGGACGCUGGAGUAUGCAGCUGUGAUCCCAAGUGGACAGGAUCUGACUGCUCAACAGAGCUGUGUACCAUGGAGUGUGGUAGCCAUGGAGUCUGCUCAAGAGGAAUUUGCCAGUGUGAAGAAGGCUGGGUAGGACCAACAUGUGAGGAACGCUCCUGUCAUUCUCAUUGUACUGAGCAUGGCCAAUGCAAAGAUGGAAAAUGUGAGUGUAGCCCUGGAUGGGAGGGCGACCACUGCACAAUUGCUCACUACUUAGAUGCUGUCCGAGAUGGCUGCCCAGGGCUCUGCUUUGGAAAUGGACGAUGUACCCUGGAUCAAAAUGGUUGGCACUGUGUGUGUCAGGUGGGUUGGAGUGGGACAGGCUGCAAUGUUGUCAUGGAAAUGCUUUGUGGAGAUAACUUGGACAAUGAUGGAGAUGGUUUAACCGACUGUGUGGAUCCUGACUGUUGUCAACAAAGCAACUGUUAUAUAAGUCCUCUCUGCCAGGGCUCACCAGAUCCUCUUGACCUCAUUCAGCAAAGCCAAACUCUCUUCUCUCAGCACACUUCAAGACUUUUUUAUGAUCGAAUCAAAUUCCUCAUUGGCAAGGACAGUACUCAUGUCAUUCCUCCUGAGGUGUCAUUUGACAGCAGGCGUGCCUGUGUGAUUCGAGGCCAAGUGGUGGCCAUAGAUGGAACUCCUCUAGUGGGAGUGAAUGUCAGUUUCUUGCACCACAGUGAUUAUGGGUUUACCAUCAGCCGGCAAGAUGGAAGCUUUGACCUCGUGGCCAUCGGUGGCAUCUCUGUCAUCUUAAUCUUCGACCGAUCCCCUUUCCUGCCUGAGAAGAGAACACUCUGGUUGCCUUGGAAUCAGUUUAUUGUGGUAGAGAAAGUCACCAUGCAGAGAGUUGUAUCAGACCCGCCAUCCUGCGAUAUCUCCAACUUUAUCAGCCCAAACCCUAUUGUGCUUCCUUCACCGCUCACAUCAUUUGGAGGGUCCUGUCCAGAGAGGGGAACUAUUGUUCCUGAGCUGCAGGUUGUACAGGAGGAAAUUCCCAUUCCCUCCAGCUUUGUGAGGCUGAGUUACCUGAGCAGCCGCACCCCUGGGUAUAAAACCCUGCUACGGAUCCUUCUGACACAUUCAACGAUUCCUGUAGGCAUGAUAAAAGUACACCUCACAGUAGCUGUGGAAGGGCGACUCACACAGAAGUGGUUUCCCGCCGCAAUUAAUCUUGUCUACACAUUUGCUUGGAACAAGACCGACAUCUAUGGACAGAAGGUUUGGGGCCUGGCAGAGGCUUUGGUAUCUGUGGGAUAUGAAUAUGAAACGUGCCCUGACUUUAUUCUCUGGGAGCAAAGGACAGUCGUUUUACAAGGUUUUGAGAUGGAUGCUUCUAACCUAGGAGGCUGGUCUUUGAAUAAGCAUCACAUUUUGAAUCCUCAAAGUGGAAUCAUACAUAAAGGGAAUGGAGAAAAUAUGUUCAUUUCCCAGCAGCCCCCAGUCAUAUCAACCAUAAUGGGUAAUGGACACCAAAGGAGUGUAGCCUGCACCAACUGCAAUGGCCCAGCCCACAACAACAAACUCUUUGCUCCUGUCGCCUUAGCUUCUGGCCCUGAUGGCAGUGUGUAUGUUGGCGACUUCAAUUUUGUAAGGAGAAUAUUUCCCUCGGGAAACUCCGUUAGUAUUUUGGAAUUAAGAAACAGAGAUACCAGACAUAGCACAAGUCCUGCUCACAAAUACUAUCUGGCUAUGGACCCUGUGUCUGAAUCACUCUAUCUAUCAGACACCAAUACUCGCAAAGUCUACAAGUUGAAAUCUCUUGUGGAGACGAAAGAUCUGUCCAAGAAUUUUGAAGUGGUGGCAGGAACUGGUGAUCAGUGCCUUCCCUUUGACCAGAGUCAUUGUGGAGAUGGUGGGAGAGCAUCGGAAGCUUCACUGAAUAGCCCUCGAGAUGACAGCUCUCCAAGAAGGAGUGUCAUAGUACUGAUGGUUGACAAUGGGUUACUCCCACCUGAGCAUGUUACAGGAGACCUGCUGAAGGGGCAAUACCGCAUCACAGUUGAUAGGCAUGGAUUUAUUUACUUUGUGGAUGGGACUAUGAUUCGCAAAAUUGAUGAGAAUGCUGUGAUCACAACUGUAAUCGGCUCAAAUGGUCUGACUUCCACACAACCACUGAGCUGUGACUCAGGAAUGGACAUCACUCAGGUGCGAUUAGAGUGGCCAACAGACCUUGCAGUAAAUCCUAUGGACAAUUCAUUGUAUGUCUUGGAUAACAACAUUGUGCUGCAAAUUUCUGAGAACAGGCGUGUUCGGAUCAUCGCAGGACGCCCCAUUCACUGCCAGGUGCCAGGCAUCGAUCAUUUCCUGGUCAGCAAGGUAGCAAUUCACUCCACUCUAGAGUCAGCGAGGGCCAUCAGUGUCUCCCACAGCGGGCUGCUCUUCAUAGCUGAAACAGACGAGAGGAAAGUAAACCGCAUUCAGCAAGUAACCACCAAUGGGGAGAUCUACAUCAUCGCUGGUGCCCCCACUGACUGUGACUGCAAAAUUGAUCCAAACUGUGACUGUUUUUCAGGUGAUGGUGGCUAUGCCAAAGAUGCAAAGAUGAAAGCCCCUUCCUCCUUAGCAGUGUCGCCUGAUGGAACCCUCUAUGUGGCAGACCUCGGAAAUGUUCGAAUUCGUACCAUCAGCAGGAACCAAGCCCACCUGAAUGACAUGAACAUUUAUGAGAUUGCUUCACCCGCUGAUCAGGAACUGUACCAGUUCACUGUAAAUGGAACCCACCUACACACCCUGAACUUGAUAACAAGGGACUAUGUUUAUAACUUCACCUACAAUUCUGAAGGUGACUUGGGCGCGAUUACCAGCAGCAAUGGCAAUUCAGUGCACAUUCGCCGUGAUGCAGGCGGAAUGCCGCUAUGGCUUGUGGUGCCUGGCGGACAAGUAUACUGGCUGACUAUAAGCAGCAAUGGAGUCCUGAAAAGAGUGUCAGCCCAAGGCUAUAAUCUGGCCUUAAUGACCUAUCCAGGAAACACAGGGCUUCUGGCUACCAAAAGUAACGAAAAUGGAUGGACAACCGUUUAUGAGUAUGACCCCGAGGGACACCUGACCAAUGCAACGUUUCCCACUGGAGAGGUCAGCAGCUUCCACAGUGACCUGGAGAAGCUGACAAAAGUGGAGCUAGAUACUUCCAACCGUGAAAAUGUCCUCAUGUCAACCAACUUGACGGCAACUAGUACCAUAUAUAUUUUAAAACAAGAAAAUACUCAAAGUACCUAUCGGGUGAAUCCAGAUGGUUCCCUGCGUGUCACUUUUGCCAGCGGGAUGGAGAUCGGCCUCAGCUCAGAGCCCCACAUCCUGGCAGGGGCAGUCAACCCUACCCUGGGCAAAUGCAACAUCUCAUUGCCCGGAGAGCACAAUGCAAACCUCAUCGAGUGGCGGCAGAGGAAGGAGCAAAACAAAGGCAAUGUUUCGGCUUUUGAAAGGAGGCUGAGGGCCCACAACAGAAACCUACUCUCCAUAGAUUUUGAUCAUAUAACCCGCACAGGAAAGAUCUAUGAUGACCAUCGAAAAUUCACCCUUCGAAUUCUUUAUGACCAGACUGGGCGACCCAUUCUGUGGUCUCCUGUAAGCAGAUAUAAUGAAGUGAACAUCACAUAUUCACCUUCGGGAUUGGUGACGUUUAUUCAAAGAGGAACGUGGAAUGAAAAAAUGGAAUAUGACCAGAGUGGGAAAAUUAUUUCAAGAACUUGGGCUGAUGGGAAAAUUUGGAGCUAUACCUACUUAGAAAAAUCUGUGAUGCUUCUCCUACACAGCCAGCGGCGUUACAUCUUUGAGUAUGACCAACCAGAUUGUCUGCUCUCAGUCACCAUGCCUAGCAUGGUGCGUCACAGCUUACAAACCAUGCUUUCAGUGGGCUACUACCGGAACAUCUACACCCCACCGGACAGUAGCACUUCUUUUAUCCAAGACUAUAGUCGAGAUGGCCGAUUGCUACAGACCCUGCAUCUGGGGACAGGGCGCAGAGUCUUAUACAAGUACACCAAGCAAGCAAGGCUUUCUGAGGUUCUCUAUGAUACCACUCAGGUCACAUUAACAUAUGAAGAGUCUUCUGGAGUGAUUAAGACAAUACACCUGAUGCAUGACGGAUUCAUCUGCACAAUCAGAUACAGGCAAACAGGACCUCUUAUUGGACGCCAGAUUUUCAGAUUCAGUGAAGAAGGCCUUGUGAAUGCACGGUUCGACUACAGCUACAACAAUUUCCGAGUCACAAGCAUGCAAGCUGUAAUCAAUGAAACCCCUUUGCCUAUAGAUCUUUACCGAUAUGUUGAUGUCUCUGGCAGAACAGAGCAGUUUGGAAAAUUCAGUGUAAUUAAUUACGAUUUAAAUCAGGUCAUAACUACUACAGUGAUGAAACACACCAAAAUCUUCAGUGCCAAUGGACAAGUCAUUGAAGUCCAAUAUGAAAUCCUAAAGGCAAUUGCCUACUGGAUGACCAUUCAAUAUGAUAAUGUGGGCCGCAUGGUAAUAUGUGACAUAAGGGUAGGAGUAGAUGCCAAUAUAACAAGGUACUUCUAUGAAUACGAUGCUGAUGGGCAACUUCAGACUGUUUCUGUAAAUGACAAAACCCAGUGGCGUUAUAGUUACGAUCUGAAUGGAAACAUCAACCUCUUAAGCCAUGGGAAGAGUGCUCGUCUUACUCCUCUCCGAUAUGACCUCCGAGACCGCAUCACCAGAUUAGGAGAAAUUCAGUAUAAAAUGGAUGAAGAUGGCUUUCUGAGGCAGAGGGGAAAUGAUAUUUUUGAAUAUAAUUCUAAUGGCCUGCUGCAGAAAGCCUACAAUAAGGCUUCUGGCUGGACUGUGCAGUAUUACUAUGAUGGGCUUGGGCGACGUGUCGCGAGUAAGUCCAGCCUAGGGCAGCACCUUCAGUUCUUUUAUGCAGACCUUACCAACCCCAUAAGAGUUACUCAUUUGUACAACCACACAAGCUCGGAGAUUACAUCUCUGUAUUAUGAUCUCCAAGGUCACCUUAUUGCCAUGGAGUUAAGCAGUGGUGAAGAAUAUUAUGUAGCCUGUGAUAAUACAGGUACCCCACUAGCUGUGUUCAGCAGCCGAGGUCAGGUCAUAAAGGAGAUACUAUACACACCUUAUGGCGAUAUCUAUCAUGACACUUACCCUGACUUUCAGGUCAUUAUUGGUUUUCAUGGAGGACUCUAUGAUUUCCUUACUAAAUUAGUGCACCUGGGGCAAAGGGAUUAUGAUGUUGUUGCUGGCAGAUGGACAACGCCUAAUCAUCACAUAUGGAAACAGUUGAACCUCCUUCCUAAACCAUUCAACCUCUACUCCUUUGAAAAUAACUACCCAGUUGGCAAAAUUCAAGAUGUUGCAAAGUAUACCACAGACAUCAGAAGUUGGUUGGAGCUAUUUGGUUUCCAAUUACACAAUGUACUACCUGGAUUUCCCAAACCUGAAUUAGAAAAUUUAGAAUUAACUUACGAGCUUCUACGGCUUCAGACAAAAACUCAAGAGUGGGAUCCUGGAAAGACUAUCCUGGGCAUUCAGUGUGAACUCCAGAAACAGCUCAGGAAUUUCAUUUCCUUGGACCAACUACCUAUGACUCCCCGAUACAAUGAUGGACGGUGCCUUGAAGGAGGGAAGCAACCAAGGUUUGCUGCUGUCCCUUCUGUUUUUGGGAAAGGUAUAAAAUUUGCCAUCAAGGAUGGCAUAGUAACAGCUGAUAUUAUAGGAGUAGCCAAUGAAGAUAGCAGGCGGCUUGCUGCCAUUCUCAAUAAUGCCCAUUACCUGGAAAACCUACAUUUUACCAUAGAGGGGAGGGACACUCACUACUUCAUUAAGCUUGGGUCUCUGGAGGAAGACCUGGUGCUCAUCGGUAACACUGGGGGGAGGCGGAUUCUGGAGAAUGGUGUCAAUGUCACUGUGUCCCAGAUGACUUCUGUGUUGAAUGGGAGGACUAGACGGUUUGCAGAUAUUCAGCUCCAGCAUGGAGCCCUGUGCUUCAACAUCCGGUAUGGGACAACUGUCGAAGAGGAAAAGAAUCACGUGUUGGAGAUUGCCAGACAGCGCGCAGUGGCCCAGGCCUGGACUAAGGAACAAAGAAGGCUGCAAGAGGGGGAAGAGGGGAUUAGGGCAUGGACAGAAGGGGAAAAGCAGCAGCUUUUGAGCACUGGGCGGGUACAAGGUUACGAUGGGUAUUUUGUUUUGUCUGUUGAGCAGUAUUUAGAACUUUCUGACAGUGCCAAUAAUAUUCACUUUAUGAGACAGAGCGAAAUAGGCAGGAGGUAACAAAAAUAUCUCUGCCUUUGCGUCACCAAAGACUGCCUGUUUUUAAAACAUAAAAUGGUUUAUUGUAUUGGUUUUCUAGAUCAGAACUCUGUAUAUGUAAAUAUGGAGGAAAAACAUAUCCAACUGCCUUUCAAUGUGACGGAAGAUGGUAUUUUAAUAUUGUUUGUUUAAACUCUUUAAGAAAUGACAGAGAUUUUUAGUUCUUGUGUGGCAGUAUUCAAAAUAACACAAGUAGAACUCAAACAGCUAAAAACAGUUUUCAGAAAGCACCACUUUCAAUUUGCCGAGCCAUGCAUAUGUUCCAAUAUCCAGAAAGAACCCAAGGUUCUCUAUCUCUAUUGUGAGAAGCAGUUUCAUCCUUAACUGUUGGCAGAACUUACGGGCUAUUUGAAUAGGUGGUGCAAUAGUAUCUGAAACUUGCCUUUCGAAAGACUGCCAGCCCUUUGACGUUUUCCAGAUCUGUUAUAGGAAACUUAAAAACAGGUGUAAAAUGUCUUCAGCCACCAUCUCCUAGAGUGAGGACCCAAUUGCCCUUCCUUCUUGAUUAUUCCUCCUUGCUUGUUAAAGUAAAUGCCAUAUUGUUGUGCUGUGUUUUGGCGUGUGGUGGCUGGGUUCUGUCUACCAUGCUUCCCUGUGGGUGUGGUAACCAGACUGUAUAGCCGCUAUUUGCUCGUGUGUACAUGAUACCAAAGCAGCUGGCCAGCGUGACCUCUCUCACACGACCUGUUUUGACUCAAUUUUUUACUAAAAGUUGUUCAGCUGUAUUGGUAUCAUGUAAACAUAGCUUUUAUUAACCUGGGUAGGAAUUUCUCAUUUAUAUAUAGGAUGUGUUUUGGUCAUAGUUUCACAUUAGUGAUUCAGUAUCUAUACACUGACCCAAUGGUUUUGUGCACAUGAACGGUAAUUUACUUAAAAGUAUGAUUCUGGUACAAAAACAAACAAAGGCUUUAGCAGGCAUACGUGUCUGGGAUGCCGAUACAUACAUUAACUACUACUGCAGAAAUUCAUAAGAGCCAAAACCUUAAAAAAAUAGACCUGGUACUUAAGUGAAAGUACUAAAGGGAAGACCAGACCAAACAUCACAGCAGUUGCUGCCACAUUGUUUCAGCCCACUUAGAUUUAUCUUUCAAAUGUACAAUUCUGUAUUGAACAUCUCCCAGCCAUCUUCAGGAAAUCGAAUCAAGUAAAUCCUUUCCAACCGAAAACAUUUCAACUAACUAUAGAGAGGCAGACUCAUUUUUACUAAAAUAAUUUAUACAGUUAGUUAUUUUCGUUCUCCGUACUUACCCAUUUAUCUUUAUUUAAUCGUCUCUACUGCCUAGGAAAAUAACUAUUUUCCAGGACGGGUUAUUUGUUCUGCGAUCAUUUAAAAUUUGGAGAAAGGUCAGGAUUAGUGUUAAUAUCAGCUGCAGUUUCUCAAUCUCUAGGAAUCCUGCAGUAAAACAAGCCCCUUGGUGAGCUGGAAGAUUUGUGCCCAGUGACAAAGAGAUAGUUUGUAAAAUGCUGUGUAAUUGUAAGUUACCACAAAUGAAAAUACAUGACAGCACAAUGUGGCCCGUAGAAAAUUCCCCUGAGCCAGCUUCUGCACUUUCAUCACCGAAUCUGAACAUUUGCUAUGUCUGAAGGCAAAUUUAUGAUGGAAUGUUAGUUUGGAUUCUUUCCAGAUGCUACCUAAAUGCAGUGUGGGGUCAUUGCCUUGCUUUGCGAUGACAGUUUCUUUGAAAAUAUGCAAAGUCAUAAGCUCAUGUUAAGGUUUUUCAAGAGUCUGCCUCCUACUACACAAAGGAAAGCAAGGGAAAGGAAAUGACCCUGGCAAACAGUAGGGAAGGGUGUAUUCAAACAUUUCAUUUUCAAAACCUUCGGGUUAGAAUACCACUUACACAUGUAUUCUGAGAGACAGAAUUCAUGAGGAACUCAUCUCUCUUUAUAACUGGAAACACACCAGCUUGAUAUAUUGCUAAUCCAUACUAAAAUCAUAUUAUUGGGUUUUUUCUGAAUCAGGCCUGUAUUAAUGGUACAGUAUUUAUUCAGAAUGGAAUUCUAAAAUUACUAACAAACUUGUUGAAAAUUUGAAUACCUCCACACCAACCUAAAAAUGGACCUUAAGUUCCUAGAACCUCUGAUGUUCUUUUAAAUUAAUGGAAAAAUAAUUUGUGAACUGUAUAUAGAGAGUGCAUUCAUAAAUGUGAUUAUGUAUUUUAUCACAAAUCCAAAAUGUCAAUAUUAGAGUCUAUUUUGCUUAUAUUUUAAGCAAUUAUACGUUUUUGCAAUUCAUUGAUGAUGUAUCAUUUUCAAACUGCUUUAAAUAUCCAUUAGAAACAAAUAUUUGAAGCUUUUACUUAAUAGUGAUUACCUUGAACUGUGCAUUUCUAGUUUGUAAUACGUAUUUGGUUGGUUCGUGCCUUUAGUUUGUUAAAGUUACAUUUGUAUUAUAUUCAGGAAAUGCACUUUUUAUUACUUACAGCUGUGGUUUUAAUACUGCCUUGAACUAUUAUUAUUCUUUUUACAACUCCUAAAGCUUGAGGGAGGAAAGAAAAAAAAAACAAAACUACUAAUCAGUAGUAAAUCGAAGAGAAACAUUUUGGCAUUUCUUAAGAAGAAGAUGGAGAUAUUGAGUAUAUCACUUCCUAUUCAGCUGAAUAGAAAGAAUGCCUUCAUUGACUUGCAGUUCUGCAGUUUAAAUUAUUGAAAGAACAAUUCGUUUGCAUUUCCUGAUGAAAGUAAAAGCAUUUUUCAGAGAAACAUAUGAAUUUCUCAUACCCAGCAGACAGAUGGCUGACACUGCACAGCCACACACCAUUCGAGUAAGUUAAAGUGAGAGCAUAGUAGUUGGACUCUCCUAUGAAGAACAUUCUGGGCUGGAGGCAGGGAAUACUCCAUGGUUGUUUCUUUUUCCUACUUAAGCCCAUUUUGUUUGUGCUUUUCUGUUUUGUUUUGUUUUCACUCUUGCACUACAGUCUAGAGAUCCAAAUGAACUGAAAAGUUCAAAGUUUAACACAUUUAAAUAUGUUUACUUUUAGUUGUCAUUCUAAUCGUUAUUGAUUAGAAGCAUGACUCCUGAAGGAAAGGGAAAUAAAUCUCAAUUCAUACUAACUUGCAACAAAACACUUUUACCAUAUAAAUAAGUAUAUGAUUUAUUUUUAACCCAAAAAAUGUAUAAAAUAAGUGUGUCCUUUACUGUCAAUUUAUCUAGAAGAUCUAUAAUAUAUAGACUACAUAUAUAUAAUAUAUACAACAUAGCCAAAUGUAUGAAAACUUGACAAUGUAUAAUUUGGAAUUCACAUGCUACCUAUGUAGACAGGUAUGAAAUUAAGUUAUAAUUUUCAUGAGACAUUUUCAUCACUGUUGACACAGUUUCAAGCAUUCCAUCAUGUUAUUUUGACUCUUUUUCUUUUUUUUUUCUUUAAAAAUAUAUUUUUAACUAGACCAGGCCCCACUAUAAUAUCACUUAAGAGAGUCAGGGCAAAGUUUUUGCAUUUAUGAAGAUGUGUUCAUGUAAGGGUGAUUGUAAUGGAGUUCAUUGGUAAUAGAAGCAAAAGUACAGUAACGAAGUAUUGAAAAGAAAAUUUUGGAGACAUUGGAGCAUAUUAUAUAUAGCUUGUGGAAAGACAUAAGGCUACAGAUGGAAUGGAACAUUCCUGUUUUCUUGAAGAAAUUCACAUACACAUAGCUGACCUGACUAGUACUUCAGCUCUUCCACAGCCUUCUAUAAAGGUUCUUUCUUCUGCAAAGAAAACAAAACAAAACAAAACAAAACAAAAAAAACAAAAAAAGCGCAAAAAACAAAAAAACAAAAAAAAGCAAAGUAAAAUUUAAAAAUACAGAAAACAAACAACAAAAAAGAAUUCAACCAUAAAUAGUGACUAUUAUUUUCAGUGUGUCCUUCAUGUGAAAGCUAUUAAGGACCAAAUAUACUACUGUUCAUAAGAAGAAAUUACUUUCUAAACAGUAACUGAAAAUACUUAGAGUUAAACUUGCUGUGGAUUUUGUCUUGGCAGUUGUCAUCUUACAUUAUUUGUCAAAGGAAAUGUGUUUGGCAGUUAAAAAUCUUUCCUUAGAUUUAGUGGUGGACUUUAACCUCUUAAAUAAAUGUUAGUAUAUCAGAUUGUGUCCUUGAAAAAUAUUUUACUUGUAUGAAUCAUGACAACGUCUAAAUCUUUACUAUUCUUCUGGCAAAAGCAUCAGUAAGAAAGAAGGCGAAAAAGAGAAGUAUAGCCUUUAUGUCAGAAAAACAUUCUUUUUAGCUGCUUACUUUCUCAUGAAAAGUAAAGAUGUUUACAGUGUAUGCCAAGUUUUCAGUUUCUGUAUAACAACAGGUAGAGGUUCUAAUCAUAUUGAAAAUUGUGUUAUAAUGGUCUGAGCCAUGUUGCUAGGAAACAAUAGGUUCCAAUUUUGUAUUCCUGCUCUCCUGUGCUGAAAAGUGACUGGAUACUGUACAGGUUCAUGUUCUCUGGCUGCAGUUAAAUGGUCUUUUGCAUUUUGCUCUGGCUUUCAGGCCAGAAGCAUGCAUUUUUCUACAAGAGCAUCACAACAACAUGCUGUAAAUAUUUAAAGUUAAACAUUAUGUGUUGAUAUUUGAAAGAAAAGUACUUUGAAUAUUUCAUUUUUAAAAAAUAAAAUUGCCAAUGAAAAA